AGUCGGCGCGUUUGGUACUCGCGCCUGCAGAGCUUUCAACCUCCGCGCCGGCUGCGCCUGUUUCUCGGCCAGGGGAGCAAGGCCACGCGGCCUACGCAGCCGAGUCGGAACCAACCGGUUGUUUGGUGAAACCUACCCCAGAGCCUCCCGCGGCCCACAGAGCACAGACAGAAUCUCCCUCUGUCACCCAGGCUGGAGUGCAGUGGCAUGAUCUCGGCUCACUGCAACCUCCACCUCCCGGGUUCAAGCGAUUCUUGUGCCUCAGCCUCCGGAGUAGCUGGGAUUUACAGACGUGCGCUACCAUGCCCGGCAAAUUUUUCUAUUUUUGCAAAGACAGGAUUUCACCGUUUUGUCCAGGCUGGUCUUGAACUAUUGACCUCAAGUGAUCCGACCGCCUUGACCUCCCAAAGUGCUGGGAUUACGGGGUGUGAGCCAUCGCGCCUGGCCACUUUCUCCAAAGUUUUAAACCAAAGCCUUCUUCGGCAGAGCUACGACCCUUCCUCUAUGGCCCAUUCUAUCCUAUGCUGCUUCCCUUUAUAAGGACACUCCCACUGUUGUGCUAUAAUCAUCUCUUGGUAUCUCCGGACUCUGCCACUCUGAGACUGUUUUUGCCAACCAUGGCAUCUGGAGAUGACAGUCCUAUCUUUGAAGAUGAUGAAAGCCCUCCUUACAGCCUAGAAAAAAUGACAGAUCUCGUAGCUGUUUGGGAUGUUGCUUUAAGUGACGGAGUCCACAAGAUCGAAUUUGAACAUGGGACUACAUCAGGCAAACGAGUAGUAUAUGUAGAUGGAAAGGAAGAGAUAAGAAAAGAGUGGAUGUUCAAAUUAGUGGGCAAAGAAACAUUCUAUGUUGGAGCUGCAAAGACAAAAGCGACCAUAAAUAUAGACGCUAUCAGUGGUUUUGCUUAUGAAUAUACUCUGGAAAUUAAUGGGAAAAGUCUCAAGAAGUAUAUGGAGGACAGAUCAAAAACCACCAAUACUUGGGUAUUACACAUGGAUGGUGAGAACUUUAGAAUUGUUUUGGAAAAAGAUGCUAUGGACGUAUGGUGCAAUGGUAAAAAAUUGGAGACAGCGGGUGAGUUUGUAGAUGAUGGGACUGAAACUCACUUCAGUAUCGGGAACCAUGACUGUUACAUAAAGGCUGUCAGUAGUGGGAAGCGGAAAGAAGGGAUUAUUCAUACUCUCAUUGUGGAUAAUAGAGAAAUCCCAGAGAUUGCAAGUUAAUGAAUUUUCAUCUUAAGAAGUAAAGAUCAGGACUUUUUAAUUACUGUGGUAAUUAAAUGUGUUCAGUAUGUACUUAUCAGUACAUUUAGUCUGCAAUGUUUUAAUUUUUUAAAAAGUUACAUGAAACUAACAUUCCAAGGGUCAGGAAAAAAACCAAUUAUGUAUAGUCAUAAAAAUUACAAUUUAUGAUGCAAAUAAUGUAAAAUGUUUUAAAGACAAAUGGCAAAUAAGAUAUGGACCAAAGUCACUAAUGUUUUACAACAGUAACCUUUACUAUAAUAAAUACUUUUAAAAAAA